AGCCCAGAUGCAAACAGCAGCCACGGCUCAUAGUGUGGGCUGGUGUAACGGAGCAGCGGAAUGGCUGUGCCCCCAGCCUGGAGUCAGGCCUGUGUCGCCCUGGGAGUGGAAUGGCAUGGGCUUGCACAGCUGGCAGUGUGGCCAGCUUAGGCAGCCCCCUAGGGCUCUCAGAGGUCAGAGGUGGAGAGCGUGGAGCAGGAUGGAGCCCAGGUCCCCAGCUGCAGCCAUGCCCGGCCACCGUACCACCCCUGAAAAGAGCAAGGAUCGCGGCAGCAACACGAUCGGCGCCCGCCUGAACCGAGUAGAAGACAAGGUGACGCAGCUGGACCAGAGGCUGGCACUCAUCACCGACAUGCUUCACCAGCUGCUCUCCUUGCACGGUGGCAGCACCCCCGGCAGCGGCGGCCCCCCCAGAGAGGGCGGGGCCCACAUCACCCAGCCCUGCGGCAGUGGCGGCUCCGUCGACCCUGAGCUCUUCCUGCCCAGCAACACCCUGCCCACCUACGAGCAGCUGACCGUGCCCAGGAGGGGCCCCGAUGAGGGGUCCUGAGGAGGGGAUGGGGCUGGGGGAUGGGCCUGAGUGAGAGGGGAGGCCAAGAGUGGCCCCACCUGGCCCUCUCUGAAGGAGGCCACCUCCUAAAAGGCCCAGAGAGAAGAGCCCCACUCUCAGAGGCCCCAAUACCCCAUGGACCAUGCUGUCUGGCACAGCCUGCACUUGGGGGCUCAGCAAGGCCACCUCUUCCUGGCCGGUGUGGGGGCCCCGUCUCAGGUGUGAGUUGUUACCCCAAGCGCCCUGGCCCCCACAUGGUGAUGUUGACAUCACUGGCAUGGUGGUUGGGACCCAGUGGCAGGGCACAGGGCCUGGCCCAUGUAUGGCCAGGAAGUAGCACAGGCUGAGUGCAGGCCCACCCUGCUUGGCCCAGGGGGCUUCCUGAGGGGAGACAGAGCAACCCCUGGACCCCAGCCUCAAAUCCAGGACCCUGCCAGGCACAGGCAGGGCAGGACCAGCCCACGCUGACUACAGGGCCGCCGGCAAUAAAAGCCCAGGAGCCCAUUUGGAGGGCCUGGGCCUGGCUCCCUCACUCUCAGGAAAUGCUGACCCAUGGGCAGGAGACUGUGGAGACUGCUCCUGAGCCCCCAGCUUCCAGCAGGAGGGACAGUCUCACCAUUUCCCCAGGGCACGUGGUUGAGUGGGGGGAACGCCCACUUCCCUGGGUUAGACUGCCAGCUCUUCCUAGCUGGAGAGGAGCCCUGCCUCUCCGCCCCUGAGCCCACUGUGCGUGGGGCUCCCGCCUCCAACCCCUCGCCCAGUCCCAGCAGCCAGCCAAACACACAGAAGGGGACUGCCACCUCCCCUUGCCAGCUGCUGAGCCGCAGAGAAGUGACGGUUCCUACACAGGACAGGGGUUCCUUCUGGGCAUUACAUCGCAUACAAAUCAAUAAUUUGUGGUGAUUUGGAUCUGUGUUUUAAUGAGUUUCACAGUGUGAUUUUGAUUAUUAAUUGUGCAAGCUUUUCCUAAUAAACGUGGAGAAUCACAGGCUGGGCUGGGCACUGCUCUCACCUUGGUUCCUGGGGCAUCCAUGGGGUCUCUCACAGACAGGACCCCUGCAGUUCCCCUGGAAGCAGUGCCCAGGUGGCUGUGGAAUAGGAA